GGAAGCGAGCGCUGCGCAGUCGGGUGGUCGCGGGCCAUGGAGGGUAGCUUUUCGGAUGGCGGAGCGCUGCCGGAGGGGCUCGCGGAAGAGGCCGAGCCGCAGGGCGCCGCCUGGAGCGGGGACAGUGGCACUGUUUCCCAGAGCCACAGCAGCGCCUCGGGGCCGUGGGAGGACGAGGGCGCGGAGGACGGCGCGCCGGGCCGCGACCUGCCGCUGCUUCGCCGCGCCGCUGCGGGCUACGCCGCCUGCCUGCUGCCCGGGGCCGGGGCGCGGCCCGAGGUCGAGGCCCUGGACGCGAGCCUAGAGGACCUGCUUACCAGAGUGGACGAGUUCGUGGGCAUGCUGGACAUGCUUCGCGGCGACUCGUCCCACGUCGUCAGCGAGGGCGUGCCGCGCAUCCACGCGAAGGCCGCCGAGAUGCGGCGCAUCUACAGCAGGAUCGACCGGCUGGAGGCCUUCGUGAGGAUGGUGGGGGGCCGCGUGGCCAGGAUGGAGGAGCAGGUCACCAAGGCCGAGGCCGAGCUGGGCACCUUCCCCAGGGCGUUCAAGAAGCUCCUGCACACGAUGAACGUGCCCUCGCUCUUUAGCAAGUCUGCUCCCUCGAGGCCACAGCAAGCCGGCUACGAAGCCCCCGUCCUGUUUCGGACCGAAGACUACUUCCCUUGUUGCAGUGAAAGGCCUCAGCUCUGACGGCCUGACCACUGCGGCAAGAGGACCCCAGCUGGGGUGCUUACCUCCAGUAUGAAGUGAAUUGCAAAUCCUGCUUAUGGACAUAUAUGAUGUUGGAGUGUGGGAUUUUAAAGUUUACUUUCUACAAACUCUCCGUAGUAUAUUCAUGAUUCAGUGUAGAAUGUAUAGACUUUAUGUCUUCCAAGUUUAAAAAAAGAGACAGGGUCUUGGUAUGUUGCCCAGACUGUUCGGAAACUCCUGGGCUCAAGUGAUCCUUCCACCUCAGCCUCCCCAGUAGCUGGGACUACGGGGUCGCCACUGCACCCAGCCUGUGUCUUCCAGCUCUAAUCAGAAAGCUGCUUGUCGAGGGCAUGGGGAAUCAAACUGAAUGAACUUUUCUCUGCACUGUGGCAAAACUGUUAUUUUUAUGGAUUUUACUAAAUGGCGUUACCUUUUCAAGAUUUAUAUGUUUGUAUAAUCAUAAGAAAAUUGAGCCAUUAAAGCCUUGUUAUUCAAUCCUAAUAGUCAGUUUUCUAGAACCUACUUUUAGGGUAAAUGGUACAUUAUUUAAUAUUAUAUUAAACCUCCUAUAGCGUGGAUUGUAGACCAAAGGAAAUGGUACAAUUUCUGAGAAUAUAUGUUGAUUUUUUGUGACUAAUUCCAAAGUUGUAUUUGAAAGUAUGACCUCACAGUCUUCAUUUGUCCAUAGCAAACAUAUGUGUGUGUGUGUGUAUAUAUAUAUGUGGGUUGCCAAUGUUUGGUUUAUAAUUUAAAUGUUAAUAGAAAUUUUGAGUUUUAUUGGAAAUGAUUUCCUUCUGAAAA